GCUUCCUCUGCUCUGGUGACCCAGAACCGUCAACUGAAAUGACCCUGUCUGUGUAGUACUCCGGCAGGAUGGGCCUCGGAGCGUAAAGGCGGCAAAAACAAAAAUAUUAAAAAAAAGGAGAGAGGGACAAAAAAAAGAAAACCCGAAAGUUUCAGCUGCAUUGCUGCGGAACGUUUUUUAGCCAGAAGGCGAAAGAAGAAAUCGGAAGUGACGUCGCGGCCAAAACAAGCCCGGGCUUGGAGGCCUGUACUGAAGCUGGCCUCAGAUGGGAAGGCCCGACUCGCUGUCUGCUGUCGUCGGUGGUCGCGAGACCUUGCACUCUCACCGGGUCGGCCUCCAGCCCCUGUGCCCGGGAUCCGCUCGCCGCGGAUGAGCGAGAGUUUCUUCCUGGGACUUUUCGGGCACAGCUGGCCGGUGGCGACAGAACGGACUUUCUUUCCUGCAAGAGUCUCCCCUCCAGCGGGAGACAGCGGGCUCCUGUCUCGGGACGCUGGGACACCUGUCGCCUAUUUUUAAAUAUCCAGAUUCCAAGAACACACUGGAUACUGCUCUUACAAAACCAAGAGGAAAUCAUGAAGAAAUGUUUUAGUUAUUGAAACUACAGUUGAAAUCAUGGAUACAUCAACAAAUCUGGAUAUUGGAGCCCAGCUUAUCGUGGAAGAGUGUCCCAGCACUUAUAGCCUAACUGGCAUGCCAGACAUUAAAAUAGAACAUCCACUGGACCCAAAUUCAGAAGAAGGGUCAGCUCAGGGUGUUGCCAUGGGAAUGAAAUUCAUAUUGCCUAACCGAUUUGAUAUGAAUGUGUGUUCUCGAUUUGUGAAGUCCUUAAAUGAAGAAGAUAGUAAAAAUAUUCAAGAUCAGGUUAACUCUGACCUGGAGGUGGCAUCUGUCCUAUUUAAAGGUUGAAAGUUAUGCUGAAUGCAAUAUCCAUACAUCUCCUUCUCCGGGAAUUCAAGUAAGGCAUGUCUACACCCCCUCUACAACAAAGCAUUUCUCACCCAUAAAACAGUCAACCACUUUAACCAACAAACACAGAGGAAAUGAGGUCUCUACCACACCUCUGUUAGCAAAUUCUUUGUCUGUUCACCAGUUGGCUGCUCAGGGAGAGAUGCUCUAUCUGGCUACUCGUAUCGAACAAGAAAAUGUUAUCAAUCACACGGAUGAAGAAGGAUUUACUCCUCUGAUGUGGGCUGCAGCACACGGGCAAAUAGCUGUGGUAGAGUUCCUACUUCAGAAUGGUGCUGAUCCCCAACUUUUAGGAAAAGGUCGAGAAAGUGCACUGUCGUUGGCCUGUAGUAAAGGCUACACAGAUAUUGUCAAAAUGCUGCUUGAUUGUGGAGUUGAUGUAAAUGAAUAUGAUUGGAAUGGAGGAACACCUCUGCUUUAUGCUGUACAUGGAAAUCAUGUGAAAUGUGUAAAGAUGCUCUUAGAAAGUGGGGCUGAUCCAACAAUUGAAACUGACUCUGGAUAUAAUUCUAUGGAUCUAGCUGUAGCCCUAGGCUAUAGAAGUGUUCAACAGGUUAUUGAGUCACAUUUGUUGAAGCUGCUUCAAAAUAUCAAGGAGUAGACACAGUCAUCAGAAAAUGUCUGCCCUUUUGUUUACUUCUUGGUCCUUAUAAAUGAUAGUUUUGUUUACUUAUAAAUUUUUACCUCAGUUGCAAUAUUUACUGGUUUUUAGUAGGUUUUAAUAAAUAUUUCUCUGAGUAAUUCACUGGUUUAUAAUAAAUGUAAUACUCUUUUUAUAACUAUGUUUUACUGUAUAUUUAAAAUUAUAAAUUAAUGUUUUCGUGGCAUGUAAAUUUUUAUGGUACAGAUAGUUAUCAUCAGUCUUUGUAUCAAGUGCUGUAAUUUGACAUUUUCAGAAAUUAUUCUACCCUAGUCAUCUUCACUCGUGUAUUAAGUCAUUCACUUUAUAUAGGGUUUGCUAUAAAUCCCUAGAAAAAAAUUGUUCUUAUUGUUGAAUAAAAAAGUGCACAGUGUGAUUGUUUACAAAAUGAUAUUAUAAAUAAAUAAAAUACUUCUUCUGUCAGUUUGCAUACUACUUUUUUAAGUAUAUAAGAUUAUUAAAGAUUUCUUUCAGAUUUUUAAUUUCACCCUUCUGUCCUGCCGUAACACUUCAUUAGAUCAAACAAUAUAUGUAAUUAAAAUAAACUGAAUCUAAGUCAAUCAACAAA